AGCACAGAGUUGGGAGUGACUCCAGAGCCUCCUGCAAGAUGCUGUUGAUUCUGCUGUCAGUGGCCUUGCUGGCCCUGAGCUCAGCUCAGAACUUAAAUGAAGAUGUCAGCCAGGAAGAAUCUCCCUCCCUAAUAGCAGGAAAUCCACAAGGAGCACCCCCACAAGGAGGCAACAAACCUCAAGGUCCCCCAUCUCCUCCAGGAAAGCCACAAGGACCACCCCCACAAGGAGGCAACCAGCCUCAAGGUCCCCCACCUCCUCCAGGAAAGCCACAAGGACCACCCCCACAAGGAGGCAACAAACCUCAAGGUCCCCCACCUCCAGGAAAGCCACAAGGACCACCCCCACAAGGAGACAAGUCCCGAAGUCCCCGAUCUCCUCCAGGAAAGCCACAAGGACCACCCCCACAAGGAGGCAACCAGCCUCAAGGUCCUCCACCUCCUCCAGGAAAGCCACAAGGACCACCCCCACAAGGAGGCAACAAACCUCAAGGUCCCCCACCUCCAGGAAAGCCACAAGGACCACCCCCACAAGGAGACAACAAGUCCCGAAGUUCUCGAUCUCCUCCAGGAAAGCCACAAGGACCACCCCCACAAGGAGGCAACCAGCCCCAAGGUCCCCCACCUCCUCCAGGAAAGCCACAAGGACCACCCCCACAAGGAGGCAACAAACCUCAAGGUCCCCCACCUCCAGGAAAGCCACAAGGACCACCCCCACAAGGAGACAACAAGUCCCAAAGUGCCCGAUCUCCUCCAGGAAAGCCACAAGGACCACCCCCACAAGGAGGCAACCAGCCCCAAGGUCCCCCACCUCCUCCAGGAAAGCCACAAGGACCACCCCCACAAGGAGGCAACAAACCUCAAGGUCCCCCACCUCCAGGAAAGCCACAAGGACCACCCCCACAAGGAGGCAGCAAGUCCCGAAGUUCUCGAUCUCCUCCAGGAAAGCCACAAGGACCACCCCCACAAGGAGGCAACCAGCCUCAAGGUCCCCCACCUCCUCCAGGAAAGCCACAAGGACCACCCCCACAAGGAGGCAACAAACCUCAAGGUCCCCCACCUCCAGGAAAGCCACAAGGACCACCCCCACAAGGAGGCAGCAAGUCCCGAAGUGCCCGAUCUCCUCCAGGAAAGCCACAAGGACCACCCCAACAAGAAGGCAACAAUCCUCAAGGUCCCCCACCUCCAGCAGGAGGCAAUCCCCAGCAGCCUCAGGCACCUCCUGCUGGACAGCCCCAGGGACCACCACGCCCUCCUCAAGGGGGCAGACCUUCCAGACCUCCCCAGUGACAGCCUCCCCAGUCAUCUAGGAUUCAAUGACAGGAAGUGAAUAAGAAGAUGAGAGUGAUUCAAAUGAUUCAAAUGCCAUGACAUUGGAAAAAGGUCAUCAUAGCUCUAACUUCUGUAUACCAAUAAAAUAAUUAGCUUGCAA